CUCACUUCCUGCACUUGAGUCCUCAGUCUUUGACUUCUCCCCCAAGGUCCUUAACGAUGAUUCUGAGGCUGCCUGACCUUGUGUAGUAUCUCAGGUAUUGCUCAAGAUUAAUGAAGUUAGCCAAAGAUGAUCUCGAACUCCCGACCUCAGGUGAUACACCCGCCUUGGCCUCCCAAGGUGCUGGGAUUACAGACGUGAGCCACCAUGCCCUGCCAAAGUUAGCCAAAGAAACCAAUGUAAAUAAUUUUUAAGAUUCAAGUCAGUGGCUUAGUAGCUGAAAAAAUGUAUACAUUGCUGGGAGCUAAGGACUGCCAAGAUAGUCUUGCCUCUGCCAUUCCCCUUCAGGAAGUGGGAGACAGUAGGACAGAGCAAUCCUAAUGCCAGGAUGAAGAGCACUAGUUGCAACCCUGAAAUCUCACCUUUGCUGGGGAGAUGUCUCUUUAACAGCCAACCAGUCAUUUGGUGCAUUUGCCAAGUGGGAGGGGUAUGGCUUCUAUCAGCCCAGCUCCUGAGAUUAAUUGUCUUAUCUCCAUUCCCUUCCUCUCCAAUCUGCCUUCAGAGCGUGGAGCUGCCCGUUUGUCCCCUCACUGCCUUCUCUCUUUCCCCAGGAAACCUUCCCAUGGCUGCAGAGCUGCCUCUAAAGCAAGACUAGAGGCAAAGCCAGCCAACAGCCCCUUCCCCUCCCAUCCCAGCUUGGCCCACAUCACCCAGUUCCGAAUGAUGGUGUCUCUGGGACAUUUAGCCAAAGGAGCCAGCCUGGACGAUCUCAUUGACAGCUGCAUUCAAUCUUUUGAUGCAGAUGGAAACCUGUGUCGAAGUAACCAACUGUUGCAAGUCAUGCUGACCAUGCACCGAAUUGUCAUCUCCUCUGCAGAACUGCUCCAAAAAGUUAUCACCCUCUAUAAGGAUGCUUUGGCAAAGAAUUCACCAGGACUUUGCCUGAAGAUCUGUUAUUUUGUAAGGUAUUGGAUAACAGAAUUCUGGGUCAUGUUUAAAAUGGACGCCAGCUUGACAGACACUAUGGAGGAGUUUCAGGAACUGGUGAAAGCUAAGGGUGAGGAGUUACAUUGCCGCCUGAUUGACACAACUCAAAUCAAUGCCCGUGACUGGUCCAGGAAACUUACUCAAAGGAUAAAAUCAAAUACCAGCAAGAAACGGAAAGUCUCCCUGCUCUUUGACCAUCUGGAACCAGAAGAGCUAUCCGAGCACCUCACCUACCUUGAGUUCAAGUCUUUCCGGAGGAUAUCGUUCUCUGAUUAUCAGAAUUACCUUGUAAAUAGCUGUGUGAAGGAAAACCCCACCAUGGAGCGAUCUAUUGCUCUGUGCAACGGCAUCUCCCAGUGGGUACAACUGAUGGUUCUCAGCCGCCCCACGCCGCAGCUCCGAGCAGAAGUCUUCAUCAAGUUCAUCCAGGUGGCUCAGAAGCUCCACCAACUACAGAACUUCAAUACACUGAUGGCUGUGAUAGGUGGGCUGUGUCACAGCUCAAUCUCGAGGCUCAAGGAGACAAGUUCGCAUGUCCCACAUGAAAUCAAUAAGGUUCUCGGUGAGAUGACUGAGCUGCUGUCCUCCUCCAGAAACUACGACAAUUACCGGCGAGCCUAUGGAGAGUGCACCGACUUCAAGAUCCCCAUUCUGGGUGUGCAUCUCAAGGACCUCAUCUCCCUGUAUGAAGCCAUGCCUGACUAUCUGGAGGACGGGAAAGUGAACGUCCAUAAGCUACUGGCCCUAUACAAUCAUAUCAGUGAAUUGGUCCAGCUGCAAGAGGUGGCCCCACCCUUGGAGGCUAACAAGGACUUGGUACACUUGCUGACGUUAUCCCUGGAUCUUUACUACACUGAGGAUGAAAUCUAUGAGCUUUCCUAUGCCCGGGAACCAAGGAACCACAGAGCUCCACCACUAACACCUUCAAAGCCACCAGUAGUAGUGGACUGGGCUUCUGGAGUGUCUCCCAAACCUGAUCCAAAAACCAUUAGCAAACACGUCCAGAGGAUGGUGGAUUCUGUCUUCAAGAACUAUGAUCACGACCAGGAUGGAUACAUUUCUCAGGAAGAAUUUGAAAAGAUUGCUGCGAGUUUUCCAUUUUCCUUCUGUGUGAUGGACAAAGACAGGGAAGGCCUCAUCAGCAGGGAUGAGAUCACAGCCUACUUCAUGAGAGCCAGCUCAAUCUAUUCCAAGCUGGGCCUGGGCUUUCCUCACAACUUCCAAGAGACCACCUACCUGAAGCCCACUUUUUGUGACAACUGUGCUGGAUUUCUCUGGGGAGUGAUCAAACAAGGAUAUCGAUGUAAAGACUGCGGGAUGAACUGUCACAAACAAUGCAAAGAUCUGGUUGUGUUUGAGUGUAAGAAGCGAGCCAAGAACCCAGUAGCUCCCACAGAGAACAACACUUCUGUGGGGCCAGUGUCCAACCUUUGCUCAUUGGGAGCCAAAGAUCUGCUCCAUGCACCUGAGGAAGGACCUUUUACAUUCCCUAAUGGGGAGGCUGUGGAACAUGGUGAGGAGAGUAAGGAUCGGACCAUCAUGCUGAUGGGAGUGUCCUCACAGAAGAUUUCUCUUCGGCUGAAGAGGGCUGUUGCCCACAAGGCCACCCAGACUGAAUCACAGCCUUGGAUUGGCAGUGAGGGCCCUUCAGGUCCCUUUGUGCUGUCUUCCCCAAGGAAGACAGCCCAGGAUACUCUAUAUGUGCUUCCCAGUCCCACCUCUCCAUGUCCUAGCCCAGUCUUGGUCAGAAAGCGGGCUUUUGUCAAGUGGGAGAAUAAAGACUCCCUCAUAAAAUCAAAGGAGGAGCUCCGUCACCUCAGACUGCCUACCUACCAAGAACUGGAACAGGAAAUAAAUACUCUGAAAGCAGAUAAUGAUGCCCUAAAGAUCCAACUGAAAUAUGCACAGAAGAAAAUAGAAUCCCUCCAGCUUGAAAAAAGCAAUCAUGUCUUAGCUCAAAUGGAGCAGGGUGACUGUUCUUAGCCCAGAAACUAAGUAGCACAAUCUGUAGAUGAGUAUAGUGAUCUCAUUUCCUAAACUGUAAUGCACAGACCUGAGGAACUUUACACUGACCAGCUUUAAAACAGUACUUUAAAAGGAAAAGCCUGUUACUGUUUAUUUACCUAAAAGAUUCCUAAUGUGCAGCACUGUUUUCUCUUUCAGUUAGUUGACUCAAAGGGGGAAAACUAAAGAAUGCAAAACUUUUGCUAUUCAUACCACUGAUGUUCAUCAAAAGUAUGCGAUCUAAAACAUGACUAUCAUUUCCUGACAAUGGGGCAUCUCGGUGGCCUGCCUGGCUGAUUCUUCCUUAAAACUAAAAUCUCUGGAAAAUGGAUUUGCUUCUUACCCUGUGUUUUCUGCAAACUGACUUACUUUGUUCCAGCCAAAGCUUGCUAAUAAUAGAAAACUACCCAUAUUCCAAAAGUAGAUUUCCUCUGUAUCCCAGCAUACUUUGUGAACCUGGCUCCUUCUUCACUACCUCAGAUCUAAUCAAUUAGUCCAUGUACCCUCCUUCCUCACUACAGUCAUAACACAUGAGCAUAUCUACCUAGAAGCCAAUUUCUACUGAUGUAGCCACAACUUUUUAGAGGCCUAUUAAACAUGACGUUAUCCAAUUGCAGGUCAACUUAUAGUUGUAGCCUUACAACUUACAGGCAUCAGAAAAUAAGUAAUCAAAUUAGGUACCUGGAAACAUAGCUAUUACCAUCUCAUAUUACUGUCUAAUUAAAAUAAACAUAACGCAAACAUGUUUGUCCUUAUAUAUUCUACAGUGGAUAGAAUUAGGAAUUGAUGGCUUAAAAAAAAAAGUCUAUGAAGAGUCUGUUUAACUCUUCAUGUUCCAUCUUUCUCUUCUGAAGUAAACUAUUUUGAAAGUUCUCUUUUUGAAAUGAAUUUGUGCUUAACUGUCUUCACUAUUAAUACUAUUUAGAAAUAAGCUAAUUGGAUCAGUGGCUUAAAUAAUAGCUGACUGUGUGUACAUAUGUAUAUAAUAUGUAUAUACAAUAUCAGGCAUGCAUGUGGCUUGGAAUUUUGUUUCCUCCAUAAAAUGUGGAAGUGAAUUAAACAAGUUUUAGUCAUUUAUACAAAGUCACAAAUAUAAAGUUCAGUUUGUCACAAGAUUAAAUUGCUCACAAGGUAAAAUUGUAUUGUUUGGCAAAAUCACAAGUAACAAUCCUGUGAGUUUUCUAUUAUGAAGGUUAAUAAUAAAUGGGCUCAUUUAGUUGCCUGGGCACCUAUUCACAAAUUCAUUUGUCAGCCUCUUUUUAGUUCUCUUAAAAAAAAAAAAAUCAUAUGAUCAUUUUCCUUUUUGGGGGUACUUAGCUUCCAUGCCUAUAAAGUCUGGUACCAGACUGACUUGAAAUUCAUAAACAAGUUGUCCAAUUGCCAAGAAUAUGUUAACAAUUAAAAGUUCCAAACUAAAGCCAAUAGCACCAAGUCUUCAUAAGAAUACAAAGUAUACAUACAGUAUUGCUUACCUGGAGGAUUCAGAUCAUUUAGGAAUUCUCUUUGAUGAAAGAUCAGUUCCCAUUUGAGUUCCUCCUUGCACUGAGUUUUAGUGAUAUAGAACUAGCUUGUAGUUAGUGUUUCAUUACAUUAUAAAGAAUAGUUUUACACACGUAUUUACCGUUUUCCAAAUUUAAACUCAGAAAUACCCAAAGCAGGCCUGCUUAAGCCCACUACCUGGCAUAUAAACUUAUAGUAACACUUUGUUACUUUCUUUUUAAUAGGACAAGCAUGAGUUAGGACAAACUCUAAAAAUUCAUAUUCUUCACUAUUCUUGUUUUCCUUUGAUUGAUAUAGACCAAAGAUGGUGUACUCUAAUUUUUUAAAACAGUAAUGGAACACAAUUUUUUUCAUUCUUCCUCCUCUCCAUUCGAAGUAAAGAUCCCCAGUUAGUUUUUAUAUAAAUAAUCUAUAGGGAUUCAAAAGGUGUCACAGUCCACUUAAUUAGUCAAAUUAGCAAUGGCUAAACAGUAUCAAGUACUGCAGAAUUUAUCACUGAAAUGGAUAAGAGGAAAUAGUUUAGUCACAGGUUUUUACAGUCCAGCAAGGGCCAAAGAGGUAUAGUAUACAAGUUAAUAGUAUUUGUGUUGAGCAACAUGGGGCUAGUGGGAUCACAGAAAUCUGGAAAAAAAAAAAAAAGGCUUUGGCUUAUCAAGCCUAGUGUAAAUUUCUGCAUCUCACACGACUUUAGUUUGGCCAGGUAUUUAUCUGCCAAAACAAGGACAAAUCUUGUUGUAUUAACAGCAGGGUCACUUCUCAUUUUCUUUGCUGACUUACCUUUUUACUGACCGUUGUGAAUUUCUGUCUCAAAAUGUAUAAUAUAGAAAUGCAAGAAAAAAACAAAUGUACAGAUUGUAAAGUUUUUUGAUACCUAAUGUAAGUUUUCUUUGUGUAAUAUUUAUAUGAUAAAAGACAUUAGGAUCCCUACAA